AUUCUAGUGUCAAGUUUAAAGGCUUGAAGUCAGAAUGUUAGAAGUGGGGAAGGGGACCUUAGAGGUGACGUCUUCCAGAUGUUCCUGUUUAUGCACAAGGGGACAGUCUCGGAGAAUUAAGGCGCAAAACUCGGGUCCCAAUUUCUAGUGUGUUGUAUUAGUUACCUUUCUCCAAAUAUUUCAGUCUAAAACUCCUAUAAGUAAGCAACAGUGUCCUGCGUAACUGUAACGCUAUUUACACACCUAAGAAAAUUAACAAAUUCCGUAGAGAAGAAAACUUACACCUGGCAAACACCUGCAAUGUACCAAACACAGCACGAGGCAUGGUGUGUGCGAUGUUGGGAUAUCCCGCUGAAUGCACAUAACUAGUCUGGGAGGCAGGUAUGUCACCCCCGUUUUACAGAGGAGAAGACGAAGGCUCAAAGAAGCACACUGCCUGCCAUCACGUGGUGUGCAAGCGGGCAAGCCGGGAUCCACAUCCAGGCCUGUAGGACUCUCAGCUCCAUGCUCCUCCUGCUCCGACCUGCUGCUGUGGAAGUACAUGCAGUUCUCACCUCUCCUAAAGAUACGUUUCCAAAUGACCAGACUUUGUGAUUCCUGAUAUCCAGCUUUUCAACUGCUCUCCAGACUGCCGUGGGUGCUGUCCCUUCCAGCCACUGCGGGAUUUCUCCUGGAGAGCUGACCUCUAUCCCUGACGCUGGCCCUCUUCUCACCGCUUCCAGCAAGCUUCCUGUGGCUCCUGCCUUCGGUUUCCUCAUCUGAAAAGGAGACAGUUCAGCCAAAGAGAUGGUUCAGCAGGGUGUUCUUUCUCCCUCAUUUGAACGCGAUCAGCAUGGGUGCCUUUCUGGUCCACUCAACACCUUUGAUCUUGUACCACACAGUUCAUCUGGGGGAACGUGUCUUCCUCUUCUCAGCCCUACAGACGAAUGCCUCUUUGAAGGCAGGGACCAGGCCAUCUCCAUGUGGAGCACUCUGGAAGUUCUGGGUUCUGUGCCUGACACAUAAAAAGUGUCCAGUGAUGUCUAUAUUACUGAAAAAUAAAUACGUAAGAUAGGAGGAAUGAUCCAGACUAAAAGAAACUGCCAAGAUCUCACAGCUGAACACUCUAGGAGUCUGUGACGUUUUCUCCUAGAUUCACUUAUAUUUGUUUGCUGAAGAUGAAGAAUUCUGAUGAAGAGAAGGAAGGAAACAAGGACAGUGUGGAAAGCCAGGCGAGAAGCCAUCAGCAUUUUAGAGCUUGUAUUAGGUCCUAACGUGAUAUGGGUGCUCUCUUAAGGGAACUAAAAGAAAUGUUGAAGGGAAUAUUUCUUUUCUGUCUCCUGGAGGUGAGUAUGGAUGUAGUUAUAUAGAUAGAUGAGUACAUUGGUCACUGCAAAAGGGAAAAAGCAAAAUUGCCCCCUAUUUCAUUUCCACACAGUUCCUCCUGUCAACAGGUCUGGGUGUUGACGUAGGAACUGCAAGUUCCCACGUCCACCCCCGCCACACCCACAGCCUGCCCUGCAUACACCACUGCUGGAGAUGUAGCCAGGACAGCUUGCCCUGUCCCCUGACCCCACGGACCUUGUUAACACCGCUGCUCCCCUCGGUGAUAUUUACCUGUCCGUGGCUGUCCUGACCAAUACUCCCAAGGAGACAGUGCAUCACUGGGCCAACAGGGCAGAGCCCCAGGGGACCACUCCCUUUACGACAUGGACGGACACUUUAGGAGUGACGGUUACCCUCUCCUUGGAUGAGGAGGGGCUCCAAGGAUGGACAUGUCAGUCUCACCUGGAGGGAGAGGGGCAGUGGGUGGGGGCAACGCUCAGUGGCUGGUGGACAGGCAAGGGGUGAGUGAGCCCUGCCCAACUGACUCCAUUGGCGGCCACUGGCCUUGCCUGGCAUUCACGGAACAGGCGCUUCAUAAACUUGUUGCUUCAAUGUGAAAUCACCUCAAUUUUGUAAAUGCGUCUGUAGCAUCCACAGGACUCAUCAUCUAGAAUUCAAACCCUUAAGGGUAAAGGCUGCGUCUUCUGUUUCCUCUGCGUCUUCUCGAAGCACUGUGUGUAAGGGCCAGAGCACAGAGGAUGUUUCAUACACGUGCCUUUGCCCUGAGACCGCAGCCCUGCCUCCCCGGUCCCACGCAGACCUCAUGGAGUGGCCUCCACUUCGGGGCUUGGUACUGCUGUGUACGGAAGGGGCGGUUUCUAUGGGAAACAUGGACAAACAGUUCUAUUUGGAAUAAGCAACCACAGGGUGCCCACCCAGCCAUCCUCCCAAAGAUUUGUCAAGAAAAAAAAAGUAGAACGAGAAUGGGCAAAAGCGUCCGACAUACUUUACUCUUCUCUUGAGGCUUUAUUUUUCCACUCCUGAUUUAGAGAUGACCACAUUUGUUAGACAGCCCCCCCUUGUCCGCCCUUUCUCUGCAGGCCACCACCGUUCCCCCUACCCCAUCCCAGCCAGCAGCUGGUCUUUCCUAAUUGGUAAUCUGUCUUAAUAGCCACAGGUCCUCAGGCAGCUGUCGCCGGGAAUACGAGCUGGCAGCAUAGAUCCACGUCACUAACUUAACUGGCUGGUCCUAUUAGAGCUUAAGAAAGAAUUAAGUUAAUAAUGAUACUAAUGAGACAGAACGUUGCAUAGGAGAAAAUAAGAGAAAGAAGGAGAGGAGUAGAAGGAGGAGAAGGGAGAAGAGGGCAAGGGGGGAGGGGAAUUAUUGCUAUUAAUUAUUAUUAUUAUUAAUUAUUCCUGGCACAGGUUUUGCAAUCACAACCCAAGGUUGUGAUAAAAUCUUGCUCAAAAUUCAAAAAGGAUUUCAACUUUUCACUCUCAGUCUUAUUCACUUUUCCAUAUGAUGAGAUUUCUAAGUAAGCCACCCGACUUCAGUCCUUGGUGCCCAAUAGCUAGGGGCUCACGCCGCGUUCAGGGUGUGAUGAGCGCCUGAGAACGGAGGUGGCUGCCCCCGCAACUCCUCCUGGAGUGAGGCCAUCCCAUCCCAUCAGGGGAGGGAGCACCGGCCCCAAGUUCAGAGAAAGGCAUCCCAAGCUCCUGACAUUCUGCGGUCGGAAAAUGGUGAUGGAUCCUGCUCAUUUCUAAUUAUACCUUUCCCUUGGCAACGACAAAGAUACGUGUGGAAGAAGCUGGUUCUCGGCUUGGGGGGGCCACUCAUCCUCUUGCCAAAUAUAGAGAAGGAAUGAGCCGCGGGGGUUACCAAUGGCCUAUAAAAGCCCCGGGGAGCAGCCAGCCCUCUGUGGCUCGCUUGUGGGCGGAGGUCUGGGAUCUCCUGGCUGUUGCUGUCUUCUGCUCUCAUCCUGCAGGUGGGACUCUCAGCUGACACCAUGAGUAGUGACACUGAAAUGGAAGUGUUCGGCAUAGCUGCUCCUUUCCUCCGGAAGUCAGAAAAGGAGAGGAUCGAGGCUCAGAACCAGCCCUUUGAUGCCAAGACGUAUUGCUUCGUGGUGGACUCAAAGGAAGAAUAUGCCAAGGGGAAAAUCAAGAGUUCUCAGGAUGGGAAGGUCACUGUGGAAACUGAGGACAACAGGACCCUGGUGGUCAAACCAGAGGAUGUGUACGCCAUGAACCCCCCCAAGUUCGACAGGAUCGAAGACAUGGCCAUGCUGACGCACCUGAAUGAGCCAGCCGUGCUGUACAACCUGAAGGACCGUUACACAUCUUGGAUGAUCUAUACCUACUCAGGCCUCUUCUGUGUCACUGUCAACCCCUACAAGUGGCUGCCGGUGUACAACCCCGAGGUGGUGGAAGGCUACCGAGGCAAAAAGCGCCAGGAGGCCCCACCCCACAUCUUCUCCAUCUCUGACAACGCCUAUCAGUUCAUGCUGACUGAUCGUGAAAACCAGUCCAUUCUGAUCACCGGAGAAUCCGGGGCAGGAAAGACUGUGAACACCAAACGGGUCAUCCAGUACUUUGCAACAAUUGCAGCUACUGGGGACCUGGCCAAGAAGAAGGACUCCAAAAUGAAGGGGACUCUGGAAGAUCAAAUCAUCAGUGCCAAUCCCCUGCUGGAGGCCUUUGGGAACGCCAAGACUGUGAGGAAUGACAACUCCUCCCGUUUUGGCAAGUUCAUCCGAAUCCAUUUUGGAACCACUGGGAAGCUGGCCUCUGCAGAUAUUGAAACUUAUCUUCUGGAAAAAUCAAGAGUCACUUUCCAGCUGAAGGCUGAAAGAAGCUACCACAUCUUCUACCAGAUUCUUUCUAACAAGAAGCCUGAGCUCAUAGAGCUGCUGCUUAUUACGACCAACCCUUACGACUACCCGUUCAUUAGCCAGGGGGAGAUCCUGGUGGCCAGCAUAGAUGAUGCAGAGGAGCUGCUGGCUACAGACAGCGCCAUUGACAUCCUGGGCUUCACCCCAGAAGAGAAAUCUGGGCUCUACAAGCUGACGGGAGCCGUGAUGCACUACGGGAACAUGAAGUUCAAGCAGAAGCAGCGAGAGGAGCAGGCCGAGCCGGAUGGCACAGAAGUGGCUGACAAAACAGCCUAUCUGAUGGGCCUGAACUCUUCGGACCUCCUAAAAGCUUUGUGCUUUCCUAGAGUGAAAGUUGGGAAUGAGUACGUUACCAAAGGUCAAACUGUGGAUCAGGUUCACCAUGCUGUGAAUGCUCUUUCAAAAUCAGUUUAUGAAAAGUUGUUCUUGUGGAUGGUCACUCGCAUUAACCAGCAACUGGAUACGAAGCUUCCAAGACAACACUUCAUUGGUGUUUUGGACAUUGCAGGCUUUGAAAUCUUUGAGUAUAACAGCCUGGAGCAGCUGUGCAUCAACUUCACCAAUGAGAAACUGCAACAGUUUUUCAACCACCACAUGUUCGUGCUGGAGCAGGAGGAGUACAAGAAGGAAGGCAUCGAGUGGACGUUCAUUGACUUCGGGAUGGACCUGGCUGCCUGCAUCGAGCUCAUCGAGAAGCCUAUGGGCAUCUUCUCCAUCCUGGAAGAGGAGUGCAUGUUCCCCAAGGCAACAGACACCUCCUUCAAGAACAAGCUGUAUGACCAGCAUCUUGGAAAGUCCAACAACUUCCAGAAGCCCAAGGUGGUCAAAGGCAGGGCCGAGGCUCACUUCUCACUGAUCCACUAUGCGGGCACCGUGGACUACAGUGUCUCAGGUUGGCUGGAGAAGAACAAGGACCCUCUGAACGAGACUGUGGUUGGGCUGUACCAGAAGUCUUCCAACAGGCUCCUGGCACACCUCUAUGCCACGUUUGCCACGGCGGAUGCUGACAGUGGAAAGAAGAAAGUUGCCAAGAAGAAGGGUUCUUCCUUCCAAACUGUCUCUGCCCUUUUCAGGGAAAACCUGAACAAGCUGAUGUCAAAUUUAAGAACUACUCACCCUCAUUUUGUGCGUUGUAUAAUUCCCAAUGAAACCAAAACUCCAGGGGCUAUGGAACACAGCCUUGUUCUGCACCAGCUGCGGUGUAACGGUGUCCUGGAGGGCAUCCGCAUCUGCAGGAAAGGGUUCCCAAACAGGAUUCUCUAUGGCGAUUUUAAACAAAGAUACCGAGUGCUGAAUGCCAGUGCAAUCCCUGAGGGACAAUUCAUUGACAGCAAGAAAGCCUGUGAAAAGCUUCUGGCAUCCAUUGAUAUUGACCACACUCAGUACAAAUUUGGACAUACCAAGGUGUUCUUCAAGGCUGGCUUGCUGGGAACCCUGGAAGAGAUGCGGGAUGACCGCCUGGCCAAACUAAUCACCCGGACACAAGCUGUGUGCAGAGGGUUCCUCAUGCGUGUGGAAUUCCAGAAGAUGGUGCAGAGGAGGGAGUCCAUCUUCUGCAUCCAGUACAACAUUCGCUCAUUCAUGAACGUCAAGCACUGGCCCUGGAUGAAACUCUUCUUCAAGAUCAAGCCCCUCCUCAAGAGUGCAGAGACUGAGAAAGAGAUGGCCACCAUGAAGGAAGAAUUCCAGAAAACCAAAGAUGAACUCGCCAAGUCGGAGGCAAAAAGGAAGGAGCUAGAGGAAAAACUGGUGACUCUGGUCCAAGAGAAGAAUGACCUGCAGCUCCAAGUACAAGCUGAAAGCGAAAAUUUGUUGGAUGCUGAGGAAAGAUGCGAUCAGCUGAUCAAAGCCAAAUUCCAGCUCGAGGCCAAGAUCAAGGAGGUGACAGAGAGAGCUGAAGAUGAGGAGGAGAUCAAUGCUGAGCUGACGGCCAAGAAGAGGAAACUGGAGGAUGAAUGCUCAGAGCUCAAGAAAGACAUUGAUGACCUUGAGUUGACCCUGGCCAAGGUUGAGAAGGAGAAGCAUGCCACAGAGAACAAGGUUAAAAACCUUACUGAGGAACUCUCUGGGUUAGAUGAAACAAUUGCAAAGUUAACCAGAGAGAAGAAGGCCCUCCAAGAGGCGCACCAGCAGGCCUUGGAUGACCUCCAAGCUGAAGAAGACAAAGUCAAUUCUUUGAACAAAACCAAGAGCAAACUGGAACAGCAAGUGGAAGACCUGGAAAGCUCCCUAGAACAAGAAAAGAAGCUCCGAGUAGACCUGGAAAGGAACAAAAGGAAAUUGGAAGGAGACUUGAAGCUUGCUCAAGAGUCCAUAUUAGAUCUGGAGAAUGACAAGCAACAGCUGGACGAAAGGCUCAAGAAGAAAGAUUUUGAAUAUUGUCAACUUCAAAGCAAAGUGGAAGAUGAGCAGACACUGGGCCUCCAGUUUCAGAAGAAAAUCAAAGAGUUGCAGGCUCGAAUUGAGGAGCUGGAAGAGGAGAUAGAGGCGGAGAGGGCCACCCGCGCGAAGACAGAGAAACAGCGCAGCGACUAUGCCCGGGAGCUGGAGGAGCUGAGCGAGCGGCUGGAGGAGGCGGGAGGCGUCACCUCCACGCAGAUAGAGCUCAACAAGAAGCGGGAGGCGGAGUUCCUGAAGCUGCGCAGGGACCUGGAGGAGGCCACACUGCAGCACGAAGCCAUGGUGGCCGCGCUGAGGAAGAAGCAUGCGGAUAGUGUGGCCGAGCUUGGGGAGCAGAUUGACAACCUGCAGCGGGUCAAGCAGAAGCUGGAGAAGGAGAAGAGCGAGUUCAAGCUGGAGAUCGAUGACCUCUCCAGCAGCAUGGAGAGUGUGUCGAAAUCUAAGGCAAAUCUGGAAAAAAUCUGCCGAACCCUGGAGGAUCAGUUAAGUGAGGCCAGGGGCAAGAAUGAGGAAAUUCAGAGGAGCCUGAGCGAGCUGACCACACAGAAGUCUCGUUUGCAGACCGAGGCUGGUGAGCUGAGUCGUCAGCUGGAAGAAAAAGAAAGCAUAGUAUCCCAACUUUCCAGGAGCAAGCAAGCCUUUACCCAGCAAACAGAAGAGCUCAAGAGGCAGCUGGAGGAAGAGAACAAGGCCAAGAACGCCCUGGCGCACGCCCUGCAGUCCUCCCGCCACGACUGUGACCUGCUGCGGGAACAGUAUGAGGAGGAGCAGGAAGGCAAAGCUGAGCUGCAGAGGGCGCUGUCCAAGGCCAAUAGUGAGGUUGCCCAGUGGAGAACCAAAUACGAGACGGACGCCAUCCAGCGCACAGAAGAGCUGGAGGAGGCCAAGAAAAAACUUGCUCAGCGCCUUCAAGAUUCCGAGGAACAGGUUGAGGCAGUGAAUGCUAAAUGUGCUUCACUGGAGAAGACCAAGCAGAGGCUGCAAGGAGAGGUGGAGGAUCUGAUGGUUGAUGUUGAAAGAGCCAAUUCCUUGGCCGCCGCUCUGGACAAGAAGCAGAGGAACUUUGACAAGGUGUUGGCAGAGUGGAAGACAAAGUGUGAGGAGAGCCAAGCAGAGCUGGAGGCAUCCCUGAAGGAGUCCCGCUCCUUGAGCACUGAGCUCUUCAAACUGAAAAAUGCCUACGAGGAAGCCUUAGAUCAACUUGAAACUGUGAAACGGGAAAAUAAGAACUUAGAGCAGGAGAUAGCAGAUCUCACAGAACAAAUUGCUGAAAAUGGCAAAACCAUCCAUGAACUGGAGAAAUCAAGAAAGCAGAUUGAGCUGGAAAAGGCUGAUAUCCAGCUGGCUCUCGAGGAAGCAGAGGCUGCUCUUGAGCAUGAAGAAGCCAAGAUCCUCCGAAUCCAGCUUGAAUUGACACAAGUGAAAUCAGAAAUUGAUAGAAAGAUCGCCGAGAAGGAUGAAGAGAUCGAGCAGCUGAAGAGGAACUACCAGAGAACAGUGGAAACCAUGCAGAGCGCCCUGGACGCCGAGGUGCGGAGCAGGAAUGAAGCCAUCCGGCUCAAGAAGAAGAUGGAGGGGGACCUGAAUGAAAUCGAGAUCCAGCUGAGCCACGCCAACCGCCAGGCGGCGGAGACCCUCAAACACCUCAGGAGUGUCCAGGGACAGCUGAAGGAUACGCAGCUCCACCUGGAUGAUGCCCUCCGGGGCCAGGAGGACCUGAAGGAGCAGCUGGCGAUUGUGGAGCGCAGAGCCAACCUGCUGCAGGCCGAGGUGGAGGAGCUGCGGGCUACUCUGGAGCAGACGGAGAGGGCCCGGAAACUGGCGGAACAGGAGCUCCUGGACUCCAACGAGAGGGUGCAGCUGCUGCAUACCCAGAACACCAGCCUCAUCCACACCAAGAAGAAGCUGGAGACAGACCUCAUGCAGCUCCAGAGUGAGGUAGAAGAUGCCAGCAGGGAUGCAAGGAACGCUGAGGAGAAGGCCAAGAAGGCCAUCACGGACGCUGCCAUGAUGGCGGAGGAGCUGAAGAAGGAGCAGGACACCAGCGCCCACCUUGAGCGGAUGAAGAAGAACCUGGAACAGACGGUGAAGGACCUGCAGCAUCGUCUAGAUGAGGCCGAGCAGCUGGCGCUGAAGGGCGGGAAGAAGCAGAUCCAGAAACUGGAGACCAGGAUCCGAGAGCUGGAGUUUGAACUUGAGGGAGAGCAGAAGAAGAACACAGAGUCUGUUAAGGGCCUGAGGAAGUAUGAGCGGAGGGUCAAGGAGCUGACGUACCAGAGUGAAGAGGACAGGAAGAAUGUGCUGAGAUUGCAGGAUCUGGUGGAUAAACUGCAAGUGAAAGUCAAGUCCUACAAGAGGCAGGCGGAGGAGGCUGAUGAACAAGCCAAUGCUCAUCUCACCAAAUUCCGAAAGGCUCAGCAUGAGCUGGAGGAGGCCGAGGAACGUGCGGAUAUCGCAGAAUCUCAAGUCAACAAGCUCCGCGCUAAGACUCGAGACUUCACCUCCAGCAGGAUGGUGGUCCACGAGAGUGAAGAGUGAGCCAGCCCUUCUGGAGCAGGACAGAAGAUAUGCAAAAUGUAUAUUUUCUUGAUUCCUGACCAUUGAUACUUAAUGUCCAUGUGACUCUUUUUCACAUGCAAUAAACUUUGCUUUGUUUCAA